AGCCAUUUGACCAUUUUACAUCAUCAUAAGAAGCAGUGUGUGUAAAGAAGGAAGAAUGGAGUUCUAAAAACUCAGAGUCUUCUUAAUCCUGCUUAAGAGAGGUUUAUGAUGCUAAGGACUGUCAAAGUGAUCAGAGAUGAAUGAACAAUCAGAGAAAAACAAUUCCAUUCAAGAGAGACACACAGAUCAUAGUUUUCCUGAGAAGAACUGUCAAAUUGGACAGAAACAACUGCAACAAAUAGAGCGGCAGUUAAAAUGCUUGGCAUUUCGAAACCCUGGACCACAGGUAGCAGACUUUAAUCCUGAAACAAGGCAGCAGAAAAAGAAAGCCCGGAUGUCAAAGAUGAAUGAAUAUUUUUCUACCAAAUACAAAAUAAUGAGGAAGUAUGACAAAAGUGGCAGGCUCAUCUGUAAUGACGCUGAUCUGUGUGAUUGUCUAGAGAAGAACUGCCUGGGCUGCUUCUACCCAUGCCCGAAGUGUAACUCCAACAAGUGUGGGCCCGAGUGCCGCUGCAACCGACGGUGGGUUUACGAUGCCAUCGUCACUGAGUCAGGAGAGGUCAUCAGCACGCUGCCGUUUAAUGUUCCUGACUAGGUGCUCUUGUAUAUGGACUGAUUUGUUUCUUCUUCUUACACAUUUAAGUUGACCUCUUUCUUUUGGGUGAAUUUUAGGGCUUGGGGGAAAUAUCGAAAAAACAUACUGAAGACUCAUGUUCUGUCAAGCCCCAGAACAAUGUAGAAUGGGCAAUAAUUCUGUAACCUUCUUAACUGUGUCAACAAUUUUCAAGUCCCUUAACUUGCAACCAAAGAAUGUAACAAUGGAGGGAUCAGCAUUUCUCAUCAGCACCCUCAUCUCUACUCUGCCUUCAAAUUAAAACUCUCUUCCCUCUUUGCUGAUAUCUGAGAAAAUGUAGCUUUAAGAUUUUCAAAACUCUGUAGUUGAGAGCUUUUCUUACAUAGAACAUAGAAUCUUAAAUUUAUAAUAUCUAGUUGUCCUUAGAAUCUUAUACAUCACUAGCUGUAAAUCAGAAUUGCCAUUUGGAUUUUGAAGAAAAACUGUGACUUUGCACUGUAUACCCAUAGCCUCAUUUUUUUAUUGUUCAUGUUUUAAUAACAUUAAAAUGAAAUUUAGUAAUA